ACAGGCGCCCGAAGCGCGCUGCAGGUGGCAACUUGGAGGUGCCGCCACCGCAGCUGCGGGAGGAGCCCGGGUCUGGCGGCCCCUUCCAGCCUCCAGGAGCUCUUUCCCGCCGCCGAGCCCGAGACUGGACCCCGGAGAAUUCGAAGGAAAGAGCCCCUGCGGAGGGACCUGUGAGCAGCCCUACCUCUCUCUGCCCUUGCGCUACUUUUUUUCUCCAAGGAAGGUUGUGCCUGCGGGCUGCGAACAAGCUCCGGGAGGGGCCCCAAAGGAAGGCUUCGGUGACUCAGACUCGGAAUCCAAGCCGGACCAGGAGGCCGAGCCCCAGGAGGCGGCGGGGGCGCAGGGGCGCGCGGGGGCGCCCGUGCCGGAGCCGCCCAAGGAGGAGCAGCAGCAGGCCCUGGAGCAGUUCGCCGCCGCUGCAGCGCACAGCACCCCGGUGCGGAGGGAGGUCACUGACAAGGAACAGGAGUUUGCUGCCAGGGCUGCAAAACAGCUCGAAUAUCAGCAAUUAGAAGACGAUAAACUUUCUCAGAAAUCAUCUAGCAGUAAACUCUCUCGGUCUCCAUUAAAGAUUGUCAAAAAGCCUAAAAGCAUGCAGUGCAAAGUGAUACUUCUCGAUGGAUCAGAAUAUACCUGUGAUGUAGAGAAACGCUCCAGAGGACAAGUGCUGUUUGAUAAAGUGUGUGAACACUUGAACUUGCUAGAGAAAGACUACUUUGGGCUUACGUAUCGAGAUGCUGAAAACCAGAAGAAUUGGUUGGACCCUGCUAAGGAAAUAAAAAAACAGGUUCGAAGUGGUGCUUGGCACUUUUCAUUUAAUGUGAAAUUUUAUCCACCAGACCCUGCCCAACUAUCUGAAGAUAUCACCAGGUACUACCUCUGCUUGCAGUUGCGAGAUGACAUCGUGUCCGGAAGGCUGCCCUGCUCCUUUGUUACCCUGGCCUUGCUGGGCUCCUACACUGUCCAGUCAGAGCUCGGAGACUAUGACCCAGAUGAAUGUGGGAGCGAUUACAUUAGUGAGUUCCGCUUUGCACCAAACCACACUAAAGAACUGGAAGACAAAGUGAUCGAGCUGCACAAGAGCCACAGAGGAAUGACGCCAGCAGAAGCAGAGAUGCAUUUCUUGGAAAAUGCCAAAAAAUUAUCAAUGUAUGGGGUAGAUUUACAUCAUGCUAAGGACUCAGAAGGGGUAGAAAUUAUGUUAGGAGUUUGUGCAAGUGGUCUGUUGAUAUAUCGCGACCGGCUGCGAAUAAACAGAUUUGCCUGGCCCAAGGUUCUAAAGAUUUCAUACAAACGGAACAACUUUUACAUUAAGAUCCGGCCGGGAGAGUUUGAACAAUUUGAAAGCACCAUUGGGUUUAAGCUGCCAAACCAUCGAGCUGCCAAGCGUUUAUGGAAAGUAUGUGUUGAGCAUCAUACAUUUUUCAGACUACUGUUACCAGAAGCACCUCCCAAGAAAUUCCUAACCUUGGGUUCCAAGUUUCGUUAUAGUGGCAGGACACAAGCGCAAACGAGAAGAGCCAGUGCGUUGAUAGAUCGCCCAGCACCUUACUUUGAACGCUCAUCCAGCAAACGUUAUACCAUGUCUCGCAGCUUGGAUGGAGCAUCAGUGAAUGAAAACCAUGAAAUAUACAUGAAGGAUUCUAUGUCUGCUGCAGAGGUUGGUACUGGCCAGUACGCCACAACAAAAGGCAUCUCUCAGACCAACUUGAUCACCACUGUGACUCCGGAGAAGAAGGCUGAGGAGGAGCGGGACGAGGAAGAGGACAAACGGAGGAAGGGGGAAGAAGUCACGCCCAUCUCGGCCAUCCGGCACGAGGGAAAGUCACCUGGGCUUGGCACUGACUCAUGUCCCUUGUCACCCCCAUCCACCCAUUGUGCCCCCACAUCUCCCACAGAGCUCCGUAGGAGGUGUAAGGAGAAUGACUGCAAACUGCCAGGUUAUGAGCCGUCCAGAGCUGAGCACCUGCCUGGAGAGCCCGCCUUGGACUCUGAUGGCCCAGGGAGGCCUUACCUAGGGGAUCAAGAUGUGGCUUUUAGCUACAGACAGCAAACUGGCAAGGGGACCACCCUGUUCUCCUUCUCCUUGCAGCUCCCUGAGUCAUUCCCCUCCCUCCUAGAUGAUGAUGGAUACCUCUCUUUCCCCAACCUUUCUGAAACCAACCUCCUGCCCCAGAGCUUGCAGCAUUACCUCCCGAUCCGCUCACCGUCCCUUGUGCCCUGUUUCCUCUUCAUCUUUUUCUUUCUGCUGUCUGCCUCCUUCUCAGUGCCAUACGCUCUCACUCUCUCCUUCCCUCUGGCUCUGUGCCUCUGCUACCUGGAGCCCAAGGCGGCCUCCUUGAGCGCCUCCCUAGACAAUGACCCGAGUGACAGUUCAGAGGAAGAGACUGACAGUGAGCGCACGGACACCGCAGCCGACGGGGAGACCACUGCCACUGAGUCGGACCAGGAGGAAGAUGCAGAGCUCAAGGCACAGGAGCUAGAAAAAACUCAAGAUGACCUGAUGAAACAUCAAACCAACAUUAGCGAGCUGAAAAGAACCUUCUUAGAAACCUCAACAGACACUGCCGUAACGAAUGAAUGGGAGAAGAGGCUUUCCACCUCCCCCGUGCGACUGGCCGCCAGGCAGGAGGAUGCCCCCAUGAUCGAACCACUUGUCCCUGAAGAGACUAAGCAGUCUUCUGGGGAAAAGCUCAUGGAUGGCUCUGAAAUCUUCAGUUUAUUAGAGUCUGCGCGAAAACCAACAGAAUUCAUAGGAGGGGUUACUUCUACUUCUCAAAGCUGGGUUCAGAAAAUGGAAACCAAGACGGAGUCCAGUGGAAUAGAGACGGAACCCACCGUGCACCACCUGCCGCUUAGCACUGAGAAGGUGGUGCAGGAGACCGUGUUGGUGGAGGAGCGGCGUGUGGUGCACGCGAGUGGGGAUGCUUCUUACUCGGCGGGAGACAGCGGGGAUGCUGCAGCACAGCCCGCAUUCACAGGCAUUAAAGGGAAAGAGGGCUCUGCCUUGACGGAGGGGGCUAAAGAGGAAGGAGGGGAGGAGGUCGCUAAAGCUGUCCUGGAACAGGAAGAGACAGCCGCUGCUUCCCGUGAGCGACAAGAGGAGCAGAGUGCAGCCAUCCACAUUUCAGAAACUUUGGAACAAAAACCUCAUUUUGAGUCCUCAACGGUGAAGACGGAAACCAUCAGUUUUGGCAGUGUUUCACCGGGAGGAGUAAAGCUAGAAAUUUCCACGAAGGAAGUGCCAGUAGUUCACACCGAAACCAAAACCAUCACAUAUGAAUCAUCACAGGUCGAUCCAGGCACAGAUCUGGAGCCAGGCGUGCUGAUGAGUGCACAGACGAUCACAUCUGAAACCACCAGUACCACCACCACUACGCACAUCACCAAAACUGUGAAAGGGGGCAUUUCAGAGACAAGAAUUGAGAAGCGAAUAGUCAUCACGGGGGAUGCAGACAUUGACCAUGACCAGGAAUAACUUAGCUUGCACAUGAAUGCAGUCAUGCAAACCGUUAGGAAAACCAGAGCCUAUAUGGAGUUCCCUCUUCUAACCCAACUGACUUGUAUCUGUCCGUGGAAAAUUUCAGUCCAGAAGAAUUGACCUUGACCAUUAAUAAAGACACUGGCAGAGAGAUCUUCCCAUAAUAAAGCAAUCUGAUUCAGCAUCACUAAACCGAUAAUGCAUGAAGCAACGAUAAAAUUACAAAAGAGCAGCAUUUUUAAUUUUCACAAAAUGUCUCAGUUUUCAGCUAUACCUGCACGUUCAUAACCAACAAUAUAAACCGUGGUCUCAUGUAACACAUAAACAAUUCAUGCCUUUCAUAGUUUAUUAUUAUUAAAGUCUAAACAAAAUUGCAAUUUCUUAGGUAACCUUAUAUUUACAAUAAAUGAAGAUUACCCUCAAAUGCUAGAAGCUGUCUAGGUCCGUCCGGUGUGUCAGAUUUUCCUCAGAUUAGAUGUGCCAAUAACCAAGUUUAUUCAGUAAACAACUUGUACUUGUUUCAUCUGGUUUUAUUACUCUCACCCAUAAACAGUAAUGACUCUCUGACCCUCUGGAAAUAUGUAAUGCUUCCAAUCUUGCUUUGUGUAUCUCAUUUAAUUUGUUAUAAGGUAGUACUGAUUUUAGCAUAUUAAUGCGAUUUCUUCCUUGUUGUUUGCUUUGGUCUGUGUUCAAUCCAGAGAGCUUAAAUUGUCAUUAUUUUGGGAAGAAAACCUGUAUUUUUGUUAGUUUACAAUAUUAUGAAAUUUCACUUCAGGAGAAACUGCUGGGCUUCCUGUGGCUUUGUUUUCUUAGUUACUUUUUCCGUGCCGUGUAUUUUUUAAUUGAUUUUUCUUCUUUUACUUGAAAAGAAAGUGUUUUAUUUUCAAAUCUGGUCCAUAUUUACAUUCUAGUUCAGAGCCAAGCCUUAAACUGUACAGAAUUUCCACUGUAAUUAAAACUAUUUAGUGUUAGUUAUAAAUAGCCUUCAAAAAGAGAGAUUCUCCAUUACACGAUCACCUGCAUCACAGCCCAUGGUGAAUGUAUGUUUCUGCAUAGCGAAAUAAAAAUGGCAAAUGCACUGAAA